GGUCCCCUACCCCCACCUACUCGCCCGCCCCCUCCGGGGCCACCCGGGGACUCUGACCCCCCGGCCUGGCGCCGCCUGACGGAGCGGGAGUGGCUCGCUCCGGGCCGGCCGGCGCCGGGGAUGAGGCUGCCCGGACAGGGUCUAGGGGCGCGCGAGGGGCCGAGCAUCCCACUCAGCUCGCCGGCCCCGGCCCCCGCCUCCCCCGCUCCUCCCGCCUGGCCGCCCCGGCCCGCCGUGACCCACGGCCGCCUCCGGAGCCCGACGCGCAGGGCAUAUACUUCUCUUGUCUUGGUUGGAUGCACAAAUCUGUGUGCAGUGCUUUUUGCCCGUUGCCUAGACGAUCACUUGGUUUCUCUGAGGAUGUCUGGUUCUCGUAAAGAGUUUGAUGUGAAACAGAUUUUGAAAAUCAGAUGGAGGUGGUUUGGUCAUCAAGCAUCAUCUCCUAAUUCUACAGUUGACAGCCAGCAGGGAGAAUUUUGGAACCGAGGACAGACUGGAGCAAACGGUGGGAGAAAGUUUUUAGAUCCAUGUAGCCUACAAUUGCCUUUGGCUUCAAUUGGUUACCGAAGGUCCAGCCAACUGGAUUUUCAGAAUUCACCUUCUUGGCCAAUGGCAUCCACCUCUGAAGUCCCUGCAUUUGAGUUUACAGCAGAAGAUUGUGGCGGUGCACAUUGGCUGGAUAGACCAGAAGUGGAUGAUGGCACUAGUGAAGAAGAAAAUGAAUCUGAUUCCAGUUCAUGCAGGACUUCCAAUAGUAGUCAGACAUUAUCAUCCUGUCAUACUAUGGAGCCAUGUACAUCAGAUGAAUUUUUCCAAGCCCUUAAUCAUGCCGAGCAAACAUUUAAAAAAAUGGAAAACUAUUUGAGACAUAAACAGUUGUGUGAUGUAAUUUUAGUCGCUGGUGAUCGCAGAAUUCCAGCUCACAGAUUGGUGCUCUCCUCUGUCUCAGACUAUUUUGCUGCCAUGUUUACUAAUGAUGUCAGAGAGGCAAGACAAGAAGAAAUAAAAAUGGAAGGUGUAGAACCAAAUUCGUUGUGGUCCUUGAUCCAGUAUGCUUAUACAGGCCGCCUUGAAUUAAAAGAAGAUAAUAUUGAGUGCCUGUUAUCUACAGCUUGCCUUCUUCAGCUUUCACAGGUUGUAGAAGCAUGCUGUAAGUUUUUAAUGAAACAGCUUCAUCCAUCCAACUGUCUUGGAAUUCGUUCUUUUGCUGAUGCCCAAGGUUGUACAGAUUUGCAUAAAGUGGCUCACAAUUAUACUAUGGAGCAUUUCAUGGAAGUAAUCAGAAACCAGGAAUUUGUAUUAUUACCAGCCAGCGAAAUUGCAAAGCUCUUGGCUAGUGAUGACAUGAACAUUCCUAAUGAGGAGACAAUAUUGAAUGCACUUCUUACUUGGGUCCGUCAUGAUUUGGAACAGAGACGGAAAGAUCUAAGUAAACUUUUGGCUUAUAUUAGGCUACCUCUUCUUGCACCACAGUUCCUGGCAGACAUGGAAAAUAAUGUACUUUUUCGGGAUGAUAUAGAAUGUCAGAAACUCAUUAUGGAAGCAAUGAAGUACCAUUUAUUACCAGAGAGACGACCCAUGUUACAAAGUCCUCGGACAAAACCUAGGAAGUCAACUGUUGGUACAUUAUUUGCAGUUGGGGGAAUGGAUUCAACAAAAGGAGCAACAAGCAUUGAAAAGUAUGAUCUCCGUACAAAUAUGUGGACUCCAGUAGCAAAUAUGAAUGGGAGGAGGCUACAGUUCGGUGUUGCAGUGCUAGAUGACAAACUGUAUGUGGUUGGAGGAAGAGAUGGACUGAAGACUUUGAAUACUGUAGAGUGCUACAACCCCAAAACAAAAACUUGGAGUGUGAUGCCACCUAUGUCCACACAUAGACAUGGCCUUGGUGUGGCUGUACUGGAAGGUCCCAUGUAUGCCGUAGGAGGACAUGAUGGCUGGAGCUAUCUGAACACAGUGGAAAGAUGGGACCCUCAGGCUCGCCAGUGGAAUUUUGUUGCCACUAUGUCUACCCCUAGGAGUACAGUAGGUGUGGCAGUACUAAGUGGAAAACUUUAUGCAGUUGGUGGUCGUGAUGGAAGUUCUUGUCUCAAAUCAGUAGAAUGUUUUGAUCCUCAUACUAAUAAGUGGACACUGUGUGCACAGAUGUCAAAAAGGAGAGGUGGCGUAGGAGUGACGACCUGGAAUGGACUGCUGUAUGCUAUAGGGGGGCACGAUGCUCCCGCAUCCAACUUGACUUCCAGACUCUCAGACUGUGUGGAAAGAUAUGAUCCCAAAACAGACAUGUGGACUGCAGUAGCAUCCAUGAGCAUCAGCAGAGAUGCAGUGGGGGUCUGUUUACUUGGUGAUAAGUUAUAUGCUGUUGGGGGGUAUGAUGGACAGGCAUACCUUAAUACUGUGGAGGCUUAUGAUCCCCAGACAAAUGAGUGGACCCAGAAAACAUUUCCAACCUGUGCAUGGGGGAUCAUUCUUCCGUCACCUAGAAUAUGAGGCCUCCGAGAGGAUGAGAAUGAGGGAAAAAACUACAAAGAAAAUGGUAGCAAAUACUAGCAAAGAAAAUGGUAAGCCAAGGUAAAGCUUCCAAUGAUAAGAAAGUAAUUGAAAGAAGAGAGCAUGGGGUGAAAGACCGAGGAAUGAGGGCCUGAGCUCCACAUGUCAGGGCCACCCUGAGAAAGUCUCUAAGAGCCUCUGAGAAAGUUUUCUCUGGGUCUGAAAACAAUUAGGGACUAUCUUAGCUGUGGAGGCACCUAAGUGAAAUUGAGUUAAAAAUUCAUAUUUUAUUAAAUUGCUUUAGACUUGUUCAUUUGAUUAUUUUAACAUAGGGAGGUUGAGUCAACUUGAUAUGUGACAGACACUGUACUAAGUAAGCAUUUCAUAUGUAUGUUAACUCAUUUAAUUUUUACAACAGCUGUAUGAAGUAGAUAUGACUAUUCCCAGUUAAUGAUACGCAAACUAGCUAGUAAAUGUCAGAGCCAAAUUUCAAAACCAACCAGAUCUGUAUGACCUUAGAGCCUUUUAAAAAAUCUUUGCAAGAUUGCUACAUGGAGGUGAGUUUAAGCUGUCUACAUUACACAGGAUGAUACAUACUUGAUGCCAAGAUACAUCCUCACCACAUCUGUGCUACAUUUUAAGUUUUUACUUUUAGUGAGUAGAAACAGGCUAUAUAAUUCUGCCUAUGGUGUGCCUGAAUGGAUACACACACAGAGAGGUUUCAUAAGUGCCUUUCUAUUUUCUUUUUAAAUAUGUUCUGUGAAAGGACAAAAGAAGGGCAUUUUAGAAAGGAUGGCAUAGUUAAUGACUUGGGUGCAGAGGGCUGUUGCUGUCAAUAAAGCAGAGAGCAGGGAUGCUGAGUGGAGCAGUCAUGAAUGGAAAUGAGAGCAUGAGCCAUUAGCAGGAAGUCAUAAACCCAUUAUUAGAAGUUUCAUGUCAUUGAAGGGAGCCAAAUGCUUUACAAUUCUAAGGACUAUGAAUAGCCACCUAAGGAGGAUGCGUCUGCUGCUGUGAUGUAUCAGACAGAGUCCAGUUGGGAGACAGAAAUCACAGGGUAAUCUGAACAGGGAAGAUUUUAAAUAAAUAAUCAUGUCCCAUAACAGAGGAUUGGACUCAGAAAGGAUUGGCUGGUUAUCAGGAUCUGAGAUUUGCUUUUGCCCUACUGGAGCUAAUAAGCUGACCUGUUAUGGUUUCAUGGAUGCUGGCAGAAGACAUCCAUGGGUUGAAGGAAAAGGAUUUUAUUACUGAAGGCACAGAAAGCAGUAGGAAUAUCGUGUUGGGGUCACUUCCCUGUGCCCUUCAAUUCCCACAGGAACAAGACAGAGGAUCCCAGGUGGAAAUCCACGGAGCUUGGGAAAUCCACUGCUUUUAUAGUAAGUGGUAGGCUAUCCUGCUCUUUGUCCUGGAGAUUUCUCGCUGCAAACACAACCCUGAGAAAUGGCCCAGCUAAUCAGUAGUGGGCGGGGACGCUCAGAACCCGCAGCAGAGUGCCUCUCCCCUUCCUUCUGCAAUGUCUCCAGCACCCUCUACCGACAAAAUUAGCACUGUGCAGACUGGCGAAGGAGAAAAAGGCUCAUGUCCACGUUGACUGAGCAGGUAAUGAAGACUGGAUUUGUAGAUGAGAAGCACUAAUUAAAAACUGGUGUGGGCCGGGCGCGGUGGCUCAUGCCUGUAAUCCUAGCACUUUGGGAGGCCAUGGCGGGUGGAUCACCUGAAGUCAGGAGUUCGAGACCAGCCUGGCCAAGGUGGUGAAACCCUGUCUCUACUAAAAAUACAAAAAUUAGCCGGACGUGUUGGUGCGCUCCUGUAAUCCCAGCUACUUGGGAGGCUGAGGCAGGAGAAUCACUUGAACCUGGGGGGCAGAGGUUGCAGUAAGCCGAAAUCACACCAUUGCACUCCAGCCUGGGCAACAAGAGCAAAACUCCAUCUCAAAAAACAAACAAACUGGCGUAUAUGUUUAUCAGCAGUACCAGACACGGCCGAAUUAUGAUAUGGUCCAAAAAGGGACAGUGAUUCAAUUCAUUCUAACACGUGUGUGUGUGUGUGUGUGUGUGUGUGUGUGUGUGAGAUCGCCACUAUGUUCUCAGAGCUAAGGUAGCUCAAAGACAUGAAAAAAAAUCUACUCAAAACAUAGAUAGUACUUAAAUAAUUUAAAGUUUAUUUUUAAAAAUCAUUUCCCUUCCUUAAUAAUAAUAAUUUUUUUUUUAACUGAGUCUUUCUCUGUCACCCAGGCUGGAGUCAGUGACAUGAUCUCUGCUCACUGCAACCUCCACCUGCCGGGUUCAAGAGAUUCUCCUGUCUCAGCCUCCCGAGUAGCUGGGAUUACAGGUGCCCACCACCAAGUCUGGCUAAUUUUUGUAUUUUUAGUAGAGACGCGGUUUCACCAUGUUGGCCAGGCUGGUCUCCAACUCCUGACCUCAGGUGAUCUGCCUGCCUCAGCCUCCCAAAGUGCUGCGAUUAUAGGCGUGAGCCACCAUACCCAGCCCCUUCCUUAAUAAUUCAGGCCUAAAGCCAUUAGGUAGUGUAUAGGAAGGAUGGCAUCCACAGUGGUGUCGAGAGGACUCAUGGUGACCCAAUGUGGGGUAUUGGAGUCCAAGCAGGGUGAAGAGGGUGGGCUACAGGGUGGGUGACCUGGCACAGGGUCUCAGACCCCCAUCAGAGUAAGGACAGCGUCCACACAGCACGGCAGCCUGGCCCGGACUGUCAGAGCCUGAGUAGGAUGAGGGAGAUAUCCACACCUGAGAACAGCCCAGCACCUGGGGGAUUAGAGCCUGGGCACGAUGGGGAAGGUGCCUGUCCAGGGGACAGCCUGCAGUGGCUAGUUAGCCAGGGCCCAGGGAGGGAGAGGACAGCACCCCUGUGCAUGGUGUGGGCUUUCAGAGCCCAAGCGUUGCAAGGAGGCCAUCCACGACGGAGAACUGCCUGGAAAGGAGAGUGAGAGCCAAGCAGGAAAACAUGGGCAUCUGGGCCGGAGUGGGUGUGGUAGCAGAAAUUGGAGAUUGUUUCCAUAGAAGAUUGAUCAAACUAGUAAUUAUCUUAAGGAAAAUGAAAGACAAGGUUUUCACUGUUGGAGAAGGAAGUUACAAAUACAGCAGAGGAAAAAACAAGGAUGACCCCCGUGGUGUUGAAUUGGAAUUCGGCAUAUUGUUGUAAACUCACGGUUUUCAAGAUAGAGAUAAUAGAUUAAUAAAUACAUAUGCAAAUAUGUGCGUGUGUGUGUAUAGAAAGAUAAGUAGACAGAUAUAGACCAACAGAUAUUCCUUAGGUAGACAGAUACAGACCAACAGAUAUUCCUUAACUCUGAACUGAGCCAGCCUGAGAAUAGCAAUAAACACACCUCAUGUCCAGGUCUUGGCUUCUAAAUACCAAUUUUUACAAAAAAAAAAAGAAUGAUCUUCACUUUGGGAGGCCAAAGUGGGGAGGAUCACUUGAGCCCAGGAGUUUGAGACCAUCCUGGGCAAUAUAGUGAGUCCCUGUCUCUACAAAAAAUAAAUAAAAAAUUAUCUGAGCAUGGUGGUGCACACCUGUAGUCCCAGCUACUUGGGAGGCUGAGGUGGGAAGAUUGAGCCCAGGAGGUCGAGGCUGCAGUGAACCCUGAUCACGUUGCUGCACCCCAGCCUGGGUGAUGGAAUGAGACCCUGUCUCAAACAAAAACAAACAAACAAAGAAUAAAAUAUCUUGGAGAAAUGGCUGAUUCCAGAGCUGGGGCAUGGAAAAUACAAGGUGAACCGGGAACAUCUUACCAUCUAACCAAAAAACGAGGUUGUGCUCAAAGACUGAUGAAGACAUUGUGGCCCAGUUGGAUGGGCUUCCACUGGCCAAAUAGGAGACAAUUUAAGCAUAAAAAUAAAUAAGAUCUAAUAGCCAGCAUCUAUAUGGAACUUAAACAAAUUUACAAGAAAAAAACAACUCCAUUAAAAAGUGGGCAAAGGACAAGAACGGACACUUUUCAAGAGAAGACAUACAUGCACCAAGAAUCCAUGAAAAAAAGCUCAGCAUCACUGAUCAUUACAGAAAAGCAAAUCAAAACCACAAUGAGAUACCAUCUCACACCACACUAUUAUUACAAAGUCAAAGAAUAACAGAUGCUGGCAAGGAAAAAGGAGCACUUAUACACUGAAGUGCUCCUUUUACACACAAGUUACACACAAGUGAAAAAGCACUUAUGCACUGUUGGUGGGAGUGUAAAUUAGUUCAGCCAUUGUGGAAGAUGGUGUGGUGAUUCCUCAAAGACCUAAAAACAGAAAUACCAUUUGACCCAGCAAUACCAUUACUGGGUAUAUACUCGAAGGAACAGAAAUCAUUCUAUUAUAAAGACAUAUGCACAUGUAUGUUCAUCGCAGCACUAUUCACAAUAGCAAAGACAUGGAAUCACCCUAAAUGCCCAUCAAUGAUAGACUGAAUAAAGAAAAUGUAAUACAUGCACACCAUGGAAUACUAUGCAGCCAUAAAAAAUAAUGAGACCAUGUCCUUUGCAGGGACACGGAUGGAGCUGGAGGCCAUUAUCCUUAGCAAACUAACACAGGAACAGAAAACCAAAUACUGGAUGUUCUCACUUAUAAGUAGGAGCUAAAUGAUGAGAACUCAUGGACACAUAGAGGGGAACAACAUACACUGGGGCCUAAUGGAGGGUGGAGGGUGGGAGGAGGGAGAGGAUCAGGAAAAAUAGCUAAUGGGUACUAGGCUUAAUACCUGAGUGAUUAAUUAAUCUGUACAAGAAACCUCCAUGACACAAGUAUACCUAUGUCACAAACCUGCACAUGUACCCCUGAACUUAAAAUAAGUUAAAAAAAUUAAAUUAAAAAAUGAGAACCAUGAACUAUAACCAUUUGAAUAAAAUAGGAACGCAUAUAAAUAUAAAUAAAAUAAAUACAUAAAUUGAAAGUUUGAUGAGGAACAAGAUGUUUACAUCGUUUUAAAGUAGCUCCCCCCAAAUAUUUAUUUUUUUCAAAGGUCAGAGAGUAACUUUCAGUUGAGAAGCCUUGCAGACAUCACCUUAAUUAAGUCAUCAAACUGCACACCAUCAGCUGGGCGUGGUGGCUCACGCCUGUAAUCCCAGCACUUUGGGAGGCCAAGGCAGGUGGAUCACCUGAGGUCAGGAGUUGGAGACCGGCCUGUCCAACAUGGUGAAACCCCCUCUCUACUAAAAAUACAAAAAUUAGCUGAGCAUGUUGGCAGACGCCUGUAAUCCCAGCUACUCGGGAGGCUGAGGCAGGAGAAUUGCUUGAAUCCAGGAGACGGAGGUUGCAGUGAGCCGAGAUCACACCACUGCACUCCAGCCUGGGCAUCAAGAAUGAAACUCCAUCUCAAAAAAAAAAAAAAAAAGAAAAGCCCAUCAUCAAUACUGGGACAAAUGAUAAUCUUGCCUAAACUAUGGAGACAGUAAAAAGAUCGGUGGGCACUAGGGGUUAGGGGAGAGGGAAGGAUGAGCAGACAGAGCACAGGGUUUUUUCAGGGCAGUGAAACUAUUCUGUAUGACACUAUAAUUAUGGGUGCAUGUCAUUAUGCGUUUGUCCAAACUCACAGAAUGUACCACACCAAGACUGGACCCUAAUAUAAACUGUGGACUUUAGGUGAUGAUGCAUCAAUGUGGGCCUCAGUUGUAACAAAUGUAGCACUCUGGCGGGGGAGGUUGAUAACGGGGGAAGGCUAUGCAUGUGUAAGGCAGGGGAUAUAUGUGAACUCUGUACCUUCCGCUCAAUUUUGCUGUGAACCUAAAAAACAAAAUCUAUUUCUUUAAAAAAUCUUACUUCACAUGAUAGGAUGCAAUGAGAGGACGCAAUAGUAUCACUUCUGUGAUGUUCCUGCCAAAGAUGCAUAAUCUGGAUCUAAUCAUGAUAAAACACCAGACAAACUAAAAUGGCAGGUCAUCCUACAGAAUAGCUAGCUUGGAACUUUCAAAUGUGCUAAGGGAUGAGAUCUGAGGAAAGACUGAGUAACUGUACUAGAUCAAAGACAAAAGAGACAUGAGGCUGGGCGCGGUGGCUCACACCUGCAAUCCCAGCACUUUGGGAGGCCGAAGCAGGCGGAUCACUUAAGCUCAGGAGUUCGAGACCAGCCUGGGCAACAUGGCAAAACCCCAUCUCUAAAAAAUAAACAAAAAUUAGCAGGGUGUGGUGGUGCAUGCCUGUAUUCCCAGCUACUUGGGGGGGGCUGGGGCAGGAGGAUUGCUUGAACCCAGGAGGUCGAGGCUGCCAUGAGCCAAGAUCACCCCACUGCACUCCAGCCUCAGUGACAAAGUGAGACCCUGUCUCAAACGAAACAAAAAAGAAACAUGACAGCUACAAGCAGUGCAUAAUCCUGGAUUGAAUCCUUUCGCUAUAAAGGACAUUAUUGAAACAACUGUCAACUUGAAUGGCUCUGUGAAUUAGAUGAUAGUAAUGUAUCAGUGUUUACUGCCUAACUUUUAUGAUUGUAUUAUGGUUUUAUAGAUAAGUGUCUUUGUAGGAAAUACAAACUAUUUCAGGGUGAUGGACCCGCAUGCUGGCAACUUAUUCUCAAACAGUUCAGGGGAAAAGGUUUAUUUAAACUAUACUUUCAAUUUUUCUGUAAUUUUCUGAUUGGUUCAAAUUUUGGUUAAAUAGUAAAAAAACAAAAAUAGGCCCAUUUUCAGGCUUGAUACAUGUUCUCCACAUCCUAGGCUUCCUCCUUCCAGCUUCCACACAGCAAAUAUUUUUGUCUUCCUCAGAUGCAUAAGAAACAUUAGUAGAGUUGAAAAUAAUCUACAAAUAAUUGAUUAUUGAAAACUGCACAUCUGAUCUCAGAAUUGCCAAUGAAGGUUCUCUGCACAUUACCUCAUCAACUCUUUCAUCCCAGGGGUAUGAGAUGAAUUUUAUGAAAAUGAUCCAUACUUGUGACAUUGCAAAUGAAGCAGAUAAAAUUCUAUUUUCCAUUUGUUCCUUUUGGGGAAUUCUUAGAAGUAAAUUGAUACCCUUCCCUGUGGAAGAGAUAAGAGAAAGUGAAUGAAGGUUUGAAAAGAAGCAUGGAGACCUUCAAAAUUAUCAAAUUUUUGAGUUUAAGGUGAUAUUUACAUUAAAAUAGCUUGCCAGUGAUGAGCCAAUGAAGGGAAAAGCUUACUUUUCAGUUAGUUAUGAUUUCCAGGGCAGAGGAAAAGUAACAAGGAGACAGGGUCAAAGGAAGUGAGAAGCUGAACAGAACUUUUAAAGUUUAAACUUAAAGAAUAAAAACACAAGAGAACCAGAAACAGGUUCAAUUAUGCUGAAUACUCUAUUUCCCAAACCUAUCCUCUACUUGUCUCAUUAAUGUCUAUAUUUCUGAGCUAUAUUAAACAUUCCACUUCCUUCAUUCCCGCCUUCAUUAUUUUUUAGUCUUUUUUUUUUUUUUUUUUUUUUGAGAUGGAGUCUCGCUUUGUUGCCCAGGCUGGAGUGCAGUGGCGCAAUCUCGGCUCACUGCAAGCUCCACCUGCCGGGUUCACGCCAUUCUCCUGCCUCAGCCUCUCGAGUAGCUGGGACUACAGGCGCCCGCCACCACGCCAGGCUAAUAAUUUUUUGUAUUUUUAGUAGAGACGGAAUUUCACCGUGUUAGCCAGGAUGGUCUCGAUCUCCUGACCUCGUGAUCCGCCCACCUCGGCCUCCCAAAGUGCUGGGAUUACAGGCAUGAGCCACCGAGCCCGGCCUAUUUUUUAGUCUUGAGACAGGGUUGAAGGUGGGUGUGGUGGCUCACACUUAUAAUUGUGCCCAGCAAAUUGUGCCCAGCAAUUUGAGAGGCUGAGGCAGGAGGAACACUUGAGCCCAGGAGUUCGAGACCAGCCUGGGCAACAUAGCAAGACACUGUAUCUAUUUAAAAAAAGAAAAGAAAAAGAAAGAAAAAAGAAAAAGAGGGUGUUGAGGCUAGCAGCAGCCACAAUUCGACUAUGUGAAGGUGUUGUGCUACUGAAUCAUGAGAGAACAUGAGCAAAUCAUUUAGAAUUCAGUGGGCAAAAAGAGACAAUUAUGUUGUCUUCUAAAUCUUUGAAAAUAUUGUUUUCAUGAUUCUUUUAACCAAAGUACCCUAUAAACAAUUAUUUUUAUCUCUGAGCCAUUAUCACUCACGACCACCUCCACCAUUCUGUUAUGUUUAGCAUGCCGUGAAAUCACAAACUACACAGGAUCAACUGCUUUUUGACAACAUCUGAAUCAUGACAGAGAUAUUAGAAAAAUAAAAUGUCUGAGUUCCAAAUAAAAUUUAAAAUACAGUAUAUUCAAACUCAACAUUUUAAGAAAAUAAUUGUAUUUCCCUUUUCUUUUAAAAAUUGAUUUAUUUAUACAAAAAUUAGCUGGGCGUGGUGGCGGGCGCCUGUAAUCCUAGCUACUCCGGAGGCUGAGGCAAGAGAAUUGCUUGAACCUGGGAAGCGGAGGUUGCAGUGAGCUGAGAUCGCGCCAUUGCACUCCAGCUGAGCGACAAGAGCAAAACUCUGUCUCAAAAAAAAAAAAAAAGAUUUAUUUAGAGAAAUGUGGGAGACUUCUUCGGUAAAGUCAGUACUUCUGAAAGAGUAUUUUCUCUCUUAAAAGACUGCAUCCACUCUGGAGAAGCACCCAGCUGUUCCUUUUGAAACUAAGCAUGGACUCAUCCUAUGAUCCAGCAAGGGCACUCGUGGUGUCACUCAUGGUGUACCAGAGAAAAUGAAGACUGACUCCCAGCACCUUCAUUCAUAACAGCCCAACACUAGGAACUACCCAAAUGUCCUGUAAUGGUGAAUGGUUAAAGAACCUAUGGGACAUCCAUACCAUGGAAUACGAUCCAGCCAUAAAAUGGAACAAACCUUUCACACAGGCAACAACUUGGAAGAACCUCAAGGAAAUUAUGCUGAGUGAAAAAAAAAAAAAAGCCAGUCUCAAAAAUGGUGCAUACGACAUAGUUCUAUUUAUGUAACAUCCAAAAAAAUAACAUAAUUACAGAGAUGAAGAACAGAUUAGGGAUUGUCAGAGGUUAGAGAUAUGGAGAGAGGAUGAAUGUGGCUGUAGAGGGAUAGCUCUAGGGAGUCUUGUGGUGAUGGUAGUAUAGUCUCUUGAUUGUGGUGGUGGUUAUGCAAGGCUAUGGAUGUGGUAAAAGUGUAUAAAGUUACACACACACACACACACAAGUGCAUAUGUAACUGGUGAAAUCUGAUUAAACUGUAUGGAUUGGA